GGUAGGAAAACCCCAGGCACUUUCGGAGGGGUUCUGCCGGCAGUCACGGCGUCGGGAGGAAGACAUCCCCACCAGCCCUUCCCUUUCUCCCCGCUUCCGCACAUCCACGCUUCAGCGCGCCUUUGGCUUCUGUUUUUCCAUUUCUGAGGACUGGGCCCGCCAUCCUCCAGGCUCCCCUCGCCGUCGCUGCAGCUCGUAGCCGUUUACAUCGGGCUUUCGCAGCACCCCUUAGGUGGGAGCGUUGUUAUAAUCCGGUUCCGGGGAAGCCCAAAGGGAUCAACGACUUCCUCAACGAAACACAGCUAGUAAGAAAUGGGGCCGGGAUGCCCUCAAAGCCAUUUUUCAGUUCAGCUGUGCCCCAUCAGGUGUCCAGUUCAGAGAAAGACUCCUGGAGUUCCUUCUCAUUGUUAGAAGAGUGAAGUUGUCAAGAAGAGCAAAUGUACCUUCCACAGAGCUGGGAAAUUAUUUUGUCAAAAACUCUUGUACCCAAGUUUGAACAACGCUAUCAGAUGACUCAGUCUAGCUCACCUGACUCCAGCUCUGUUUCAAAUUUUGAGCUCUAAGCUUUGGUGGCAAUAACUCUGGCAGUGAAAAAACCCUCAGGCUUGUAGAUAGCUUUGCUUCUUUGUCUUCUUUUGCUUCAUCGUUAUCAUCCUUCAUCAUUCUGGAAAGAUUGACAGUUUAGUGUUCAAGGGCACAGACUCUGCAGUCAAGGCUGAGGUCUUAGUUAGCUACUCACUAGGUGUGUGACUUUGGGACAUGGGUGUGGAGGCAAAGAACCAUGAAGUACACAACAGCCACAGGAAGAAACAUUACCAAGGUCCUCAUUGCAAACAGAGGAGAAAUUGCCUGCAGGGUGAUGCGCACAGCCAAAAAACUGGGUGUACAGACUGUGGCGGUUUAUAGUGAGGCUGACAGAAAUUCCAUGCAUGUAGAUAUGGCAGAUGAAGCAUAUUCCAUCGGCCCCGCUCCCUCCCAGCAGAGCUACCUAUCUAUGGAGAAAAUCAUUCAAGUGGCCAAGACCUCUGCUGCACAGGCUAUCCAUCCAGGAUGCGGUUUUCUCUCAGAAAACAUGGAAUUUGCUGAACUUUGUAAGCAAGAAGGAAUUAUUUUUAUAGGCCCUCCUCCAUCUGCAAUUAGAGACAUGGGUAUAAAGAGCACAUCCAAAUCCAUAAUGGCUGCUGCUGGAGUACCUGUUGUGGAGGGUUAUCAUGGUGAGGACCAAUCAGACCAGUGCCUGAAGGAACACGCCAGGAGAAUUGGCUAUCCUGUCAUGAUUAAAGCCGUCCGGGGUGGAGGAGGAAAAGGAAUGAGGAUUGUUAGAUCAGAACAAGAAUUUCAAGAACAGUUAGAGUCAGCACGGAGAGAAGCUAAGAAGUCUUUCAAUGAUGAUGCUAUGCUGAUCGAGAAGUUUGUAGACACACCGAGGCAUGUAGAAGUCCAGGUGUUUGGUGAUCACCAUGGCAAUGCUGUGUACUUGUUUGAAAGAGACUGUAGUGUGCAGAGGCGACAUCAGAAGAUCAUUGAGGAGGCCCCAGCGCCUGGUAUUAAAUCUGAAGUAAGAAAAAAGCUGGGAGAAGCUGCAGUCAGAGCUGCUAAAGCUGUAAAUUAUGUUGGAGCAGGGACUGUGGAGUUUAUUAUGGACUCAAAACAUAAUUUCUGUUUCAUGGAGAUGAAUACAAGGCUGCAAGUGGAACAUCCUGUUACUGAGAUGAUCACAGGAACUGACUUGGUGGAGUGGCAGCUUAGAAUUGCAGCAGGAGAGAAGAUUCCUUUGAGCCAGGAAGAAAUAACUCUGCAGGGCCAUGCCUUCGAAGCUAGAAUAUAUGCAGAAGAUCCUAGCAAUAACUUCAUGCCUGUGGCAGGCCCAUUAGUGCACCUCUCUACUCCUCGAGCAGACCCUUCCACCAGGAUUGAAACUGGAGUACGGCAAGGAGACGAAGUUUCCGUGCAUUAUGACCCCAUGAUUGCGAAGCUGGUCGUGUGGGCAGCAGAUCGCCAGGCGGCAUUGACAAAACUGAGGUACAGCCUUCGUCAGUACAAUAUUGUUGGACUGCACACCAACAUUGACUUCUUACUCAACCUGUCUGGCCACCCAGAGUUUGAAGCUGGGAACGUGCACACUGAUUUCAUCCCUCAACACCACAAACAGUUGUUGCUCAGUCGGAAGGCUGCAGCCAAAGAGUCUUUAUGCCAGGCAGCCCUGGGUCUCAUCCUCAAGGAGAAAGCCAUGACCGACACUUUCACUCUUCAGGCACAUGAUCAAUUCUCUCCAUUUUCGUCUAGCAGUGGAAGAAGACUGAAUAUCUCGUAUACCAGAAACAUGACUCUUAAAGAUGGUAAAAACAAUGUAGCCAUAGCUGUAACGUAUAACCAUGAUGGGUCUUAUAGCAUGCAGAUUGAAGAUAAAACUUUCCAAGUCCUUGGUAAUCUUUACAGCGAGGGAGACUGCACUUACCUGAAAUGUUCUGUUAAUGGAGUUGCUAGUAAAGCGAAGCUGAUUAUCCUGGAAAACACUAUUUACCUAUUUUCCAAGGAAGGAAGUAUUGAGAUUGACAUUCCAGUCCCCAAAUACUUAUCUUCUGUGAGCUCACAAGAAACUCAGGGCGGCCCCUUAGCUCCUAUGACUGGAACCAUUGAAAAGGUGUUUGUCAAAGCUGGAGACAAAGUGAAAGCGGGAGAUUCCCUCAUGGUUAUGAUCGCCAUGAAGAUGGAGCAUACCAUAAAGUCUCCAAAGGAUGGCACAGUAAAGAAAGUGUUCUACAGAGAAGGUGCUCAGGCCAACAGACACACUCCUUUAGUCGAGUUUGAGGAGGAAGAAUCAGACAAAAGGGAAUCGGAAUAAACUCCAGCAAGGAAAUGGCCAGUUAAGUAGUGUCUUCUCUCUCCACCAAAAAGAGGAAGUGCCUCCAGCUUUUCUGGGGGUCUCAUAAAGAGCAGUUUUACUAAAUGAUUGUAUGCUUAUGCUGAACACCUUUCAUAUUGGAGAAUCAUGCAUUUGGGUCACUAAUUAUCUCAAAAUAUUUCAUACUAAUAAAGUUGAAUUAUUUUUUAUUGGAAGCCAA